AGAGCGGAGGUGGUGGCGGCGGAGGCUUUGGCAGCUCGGGACUGAGUGCAAGGUGACUGGGAGGGUAGCUAGAUCAGCGUGGCCUUUUGGGACUCCAGUUCUGGGUUUUUUCACGAGGCCUGGGCUGCCUCUCACCUUUACUAGGAGGAGAGAGCAGCUCUGUGUCCUGGGGACCUUCACGGCCUGGCCCGGGGUCACAGCUGACCUCUACGUUUGUAGACCUUGGAGUUUGCCGUAGACCCAGAAAUAAGAUCGAUACCCUCUCUGAGGGCAAAUCGGGGCGGCGCGGGGGGCAGGGAGGCCCGGGGGUCUCGGGCCCGCAGCCUGGCUGGGGCAACCCAAGGUCAGGCGCGCGGGAGAGAUUUUCGGCCAGGCCUACCCGCCCCGGGCGCACGGGAGCGUCUAGGCUACUUAGGCAGAACGUGUACCAUUAAGAGGGAAAAAAUUAGUCAUAAUAUUGAAAGUUUGCAUCCCACCUAAAAACGAUGGUGCUAACACUUCAUUAGGCGACUUUAUGGAUUGUUCAUAGGAAUAUGCACUGAAGAGGCAGCGAACCUACUAACCUUUGGCCGAAUCAGCAUGAUUCUUCAGAGGCUCUUCAGGUUCUCCUCUGUCAUUCGGUCAGCCGUCUCAGUCCAUUUGCGGAGGAACAUUGGUGUUACAGCAGUGGCAUUUAAUAAGGAACUUGAUCCUAUACAGAAACUCUUUGUGGACAAGAUUAGAGAAUACAAAUCUAAGCGACAGACAUCUGGAGGACCUGUUGAUGCUAGUUCAGAGUAUCAGCAAGAGCUGGAGAGGGAGCUUUUUAAGCUCAAGCAAAUGUUUGGUAAUGCAGACAUGAAUACAUUUCCCACCUUCAAAUUUGAAGAUCCCAAAUUUGAAGUCAUCGAAAAACCCCAGGCCUGAAGAAAUAAAGUAAAAUUAAUCUGGUAAUUUGUCACGGAUUAGUUGUACAACUAGUUAGAAGUUUCAGAAUAAACAUGCAUUUCAUAACUGUCAAAUGUUCUUUUAAUUCUGAGUCCAAAUAAAUUAUUUGGUGAUGUUGA